CUCCACACCCCUUUCUGAAUCUCCCAGAAGGCUCCCUGAAUGAGAGAGUUGAGGGCCAGGAGAGAGUUUCUGGGUCAGAAUAACACUGGACCUCUCAUCCCUGCCCUGCCAGGGCCCUGAGAGAUGGGCUAAGGCAGCUAGUCUCAUCUCCAUUUCGUAGAUGAGGGUACUGAGGUUCAGUUGGUGAUAGGGAAAGAAACCAGCCCUUUAUCCUCCUAUGCUCCAGUUCUUCCUGCCAUGCUGAGACACCUUUUCCUUUGUAAAGAGAAGACAGCUGGCCCUCUUUCCCAGCUAGUUCCAGAAAGUUUGAGUCUAGACAAGCAAGGAAGGGGGAAGUAUCAUCUCCGUUUUGGGGAGCAGCCUUUUUAGCUCCUGCUGGUAAGGAGAAUGAACCUUAAAGUGGGCAAAUAGUGUUCCUGCCUUCUACCAGAAAGAACACGAAGGGUUAGUGACUGAAUGAAGAUGUUUUGUAAUUUUGAGACCUUCUCUAUUUUUUUCAAGUUCCUUUGCUUCCUCACAUUUAGCCUAAAAGAUGAACCCAACAUUCUCUCAACCCAUAGAGACUUGCCCAGGGUCUCAUGGCAAGUUAGCUCAGUCUCACAACUCAUGUUGCCUCUGAAAAAUCGGUUUGCAGAAGUUGAAGAGUGGAAGAACUGGAAACUGACCAGCAGCACUUGGACCCUUUUUGACAGGCUCUAUCCAUACCACCUCCCUGAUAAGCCCUGGCACACCGAAGUGUAGGCCCACCCACUGCCAGACACCUAGGGCCAAAGAAACUGAGGGAGGGGAAGCAGAUUUUAGAAAAGGGAACCAUUCAUAGCUGAUUAGGUUUUAUUUUGUUUGCUUACUUGCCUUUAAUUACCUGAGGGAAAGGAUUAGGAAUUUAUUUCCCAAGACGAUAGGCUUGAGGAAGUUAUAACUAGGUUGUAACCUUAGCUUCCCUUUUGCUAGAAGAAAAUGCAUGCAUGCUUCUUGACGAUUGUAUUGUACUCCUAGAUCUGGAAGGGUCCUAGGAGAGUAGAAGUGAUGUGUUAAAGAGAGUCAGUGAUAAGUUUCUUAGUGUGUAAUGGCUGUUUUCCUCUCUUGGAGAUUGUUUCAUUCAUCUACUCAUUCAUUCAGCAAACAUACAUAUACACUGUGCUUGACUCUUCAGGCACUGCAGAGAGGCCACUUAGGCAGAUGGCAGCUCCCACCAGCUCUGAUUUUGAAAUCGACACAAGUCCUCAGAAGCAAGAUACAUGUAGCUGUUGGUUUGAGAACCAUGAAUUUUGAACCUGUAGACUGUUCAUCCUCCAAGUUAGAAUGUUGAUAAAUCUGUAUGGUUAUUUAAAAAACCCAAGCAUCAUUUGGAAACUGGCAGAGUAGGUUCAAAGAAGUGUGCCAGUUUGAAUUAGUUGAAAAACACUUCCCCUUACCUCUCUUCAGUUUUUUUCUUGGGAGGAGAAAGGGGAAAAAAAGACAACAACUUGAAGUUGGCCAAACCACAUUUUGAAUUUUGAUCUCCUGGGUACCCACUGCCCUGCAUAGAGACCUGAUCGAAGGGCCAGGGUGAGUUCGGGAAUUCAUUACCCUGGAAUAACUCCUAUGUAUCUUCAAACCCCUUCCUGACUUAAACUUGGUGGCUCUGAGAAUUGCUUACAGUGACUUCAGAGAGCUCAUCUGGCAUCUCCUAUAUGUAAAUACCACUGUGCUAUGGCACCAGGUGUGAGGAGGAAUCCCCUCAAGUGGGAAGCAGAGGUGGCUUUAUGUUUGUGGAUUAGCUAUUAAUUGAUUAAUUAAUCUCUCUGACACAAAUAGAAUGGUUUCCAAGGUAGUUUCAGCACAGCUUUCUGGCUUUUGGUGAGAAGUAUGUUGCUAUACUGAGUGUUGGCCCAAGCCAGCCCAGAGCUGUCUUGAAGUAUACUUCUUUUUAUACUCAGGAAAUGUCAAAGCCGACUGCUGUGGGACUUUACAUUUUACUGCCCAUAGUAGGUGGUUUAUACCACUACUUAUCAAAUUACAAUCCCAGUUCAAGGAAAAACAAAACUCCUUCUUUCCUGAUAGUCUUGCUAUAUGCCUACACAUUAUCUCUGUUAGUCCUCUAAGUGACAUUUUGGUAGGUAUUGCUGUGGUUAGUAUUUCCAUUUCAUAGAUGAGGACACCGAAGCUCAGAGACUUGCCUACAGCCACACAGCUAAUAAAUGGCAAGGCUGGAAUUGGAACACAGGUCUUCCAGUGCCAGGCCCCCACUUGGCAGUCUCCUUUGUAAAGUAGCCGAUGUUCCCAUCAGCUACACAGCAUGAUUUGGAAGGAGUGAAAGGAAAUGGAAAAACUGUCCAUGAAGCUUACAGCUCAAGGCAAGUUUUCAAGCCAGAGUAUAAUUUUAGUUUCUGAGUUUUCAAGCCCAUUCUGCUCUUUCUCCAUUACCAUCCUCCCUCUUACAGAGCACACACAGCUGUCCCCCACCCGCCUAUCUCUUCAGUUGGCAUUUGCUUGAAUAAAUCUUCACUAAGGCUGUCCCUCUUGGAGGGUCCACAUAACUCAAAGUUUGACUCACCUUUGACCUCUGUUCUCUCUUUACUCUCAUUUAUUUGCCAAGCAGGUUGUGAAAGUGAGAACUACUCAUUUGGAGAGCUCACCAUCAUCUAACUGCAAUCCAGCCUGCUACUGGGGCUCAUAGUGUUGAAUUUUAUUUUUUUUUUAGGAGGCUCAAACUGGUUUCUCUGUGCCUAGAGCCCUAAAAUUUUAAGUUGUUCUAUCUAGGCACCUGUGCUCUGUUACUGUUGUUUGAGUGUGCUGAAUUUUUUUGUUUCAGAUGUCUCCUUACUGCUUUCUGUAUGCCAGGCCCAGUGCUGUAUUAAGUGAAUAUACCAGUGCACCUAUGCAUCUCAGAAGACAAAUCUGACCUUGAAAACAGUGUGAUGCAGAAGAAAAUAAAAAUCCCCAAGCUUUCUCUUAAUCAUGUAGAAGAAGAUGGAGAGGUUAAAGAUUAUGGGGAAGAAGAUUUACAGCUUAGACACAUCAAGAGACCUGAGGGGCGGAAGCCGAGCGAAGUGGCGCACAAGAGCAUCGAGGCAGUGGUGGCUCGGCUAGAGAAGCAGAACGGCCUGAGCCUGGGCCAUAGCACGUGUCCGGAAGAGGUCUUCGUGGAGGCCUCGCCAGGCACAGAGGACAUGGACAGUCUAGAAGAUGCUGUGGUGCCCCGGGCUCUGUAUGAGGAGCUGCUGCGCAACUACCAGCAGCAACAGGAAGAGAUGCGCCACCUCCAGCAGGAGCUGGAGCGGACUCGGAGGCAGCUGGUACAACAGGCCAAGAAGCUCAAGGAGUACGGGGCACUUGUGUCUGAAAUGAAGGAGCUCCGUGACCUUAACCGGAGGCUCCAGGACGUGCUGCUCCUGCGGCUUGGCAGCGGUCCCGCCAUUGAUCUGGAAAAAGUAAAGUCAGAAUGUCUCGAGCCCGAGCCGGAGUUACGGAGCACUUUCAGUGAGGAAGCAAAUACGUCGUCCUAUUACCCCGCUCCUGCGCCUGUCAUGGACAAGUAUAUCCUAGACAAUGGCAAGGUCCAUCUGGGAAGCGGGAUUUGGGUUGAUGAGGAGAAAUGGCACCAGCUACAAGUAACCCAAGGAGAUUCCAAGUACACGAAGAACUUGGCAGUUAUGAUUUGGGGAACAGAUGUUCUGAAAAACAGAAGCGUCACAGGCGUCGCCACAAAAAAAAAGAAAGAUGCAGUCCCUAAACCACCCCUCUCGCCUCACAAACUAAGCAUCGUCAGAGAGUGUUUGUAUGACAGAAUAGCACAAGAAACUGUGGAUGAAACUGAAAUUGCACAGAGACUCUCCAAAGUCAACAAGUACAUCUGUGAAAAAAUCAUGGAUAUCAAUAAAUCCUGUAAAAAUGAAGAACGAAGGGAAGCAAAAUACAAUUUGCAAUAAACUUUGGAUUUUUCAUAAAGCUUUCGUGUUUUCCUUGUGUGGCAUGUGAUUUGCGAGCGAUGGUGCCGUCCAAAUCAGACCCCACCGUGCAUGGUGGUGUGUGUGCAGGGAUCCAUCGGGUUCUGGGGUCAGCGGCUUGUUCUGAAUGUGGACACUCCAAAGACGACAGAUGGCUUUGCUGAGACUCAGGAGCAGCCUGGCACUGGUGUCCUUCUGGGAAUGGGGAAAACACUCUUCUUGGAGGGGGAUAAGGUUGCCUGAGUUGCCUGUCACUUGACUGGGGUUUGAAUGGAUAUUUUUACUAUCCAAGGACUUCUUUGUUGCUCUAUUUUGUUCUAUAAUAAAUUUUCAUUAAUUCUUUGAUGUA